AGGUGCUCCGCCUGGAAAUGUCUCCAUUAGUUGUCGCCGGCUCCCCGCUGGAGCGCGCGCGCCGAGCUUCCGCGCGGAGCCCUCGCGGGCUGCCGGGAGCGGCCCAGCGCCACCGCAGCGCCUAGAAGCCUGCAGCUCCGGAGCAGUGGCCGCGCCACGCCGGCCCCAGCGCGCAGAACCCUGCAGGCCCCGCCCGUCCGCCCCGGGCCGCGCCCGCCAUGUCCUACCCGCAGUUUGGAUACCCCUACUCCUCGGCUCCCCAGUUCUUGAUGGCCACCAACUCCCUGAGCACGUGCUGCGAGUCCGGAGGCCGCACGCUGGCGGACUCCGGGCCCGCCGCCUCGGCCCAGGCGCCGGUCUACUGCCCGGUCUACGAGAGCCGGCUGCUGGCCACCGCGCGCCACGAGCUCAACUCGGCCGCGGCGCUGGGCGUCUAUGGGGGUCCCUAUGGCGGAUCGCAGGGCUAUGGCAACUACGUGACCUACGGCUCGGAGGCGUCCGCCUUCUACUCGCUGAACAGCUUUGAUUCCAAGGAUGGUUCGGGAUCUGCGCAUGGGGGCCUGGCACCAGCCGCUGCCGCCUACUACCCUUACGAGCCAGCUCUGGGCCAGUACCCCUAUGACAGGAUCAAACGGCUAGGCGGUCAUCCCCAUAAAGGAAUUGGCCUGGACCUCUCUGGCUUGGGAAGGAGCCCAGGCUCCCUGUAUGGAACCAUGGACAGCGGCACGCGGCGCAAGAACGCCACGCGCGAGACCACCAGCACGCUCAAGGCCUGGCUGCAGGAGCACCGCAAGAACCCCUACCCCACCAAGGGCGAGAAGAUCAUGCUGGCCAUCAUCACCAAGAUGACCCUCACACAGGUCUCCACCUGGUUCGCCAACGCGCGCCGGCGCCUCAAGAAGGAGAACAAGAUGACGUGGCCGCCGCGGAACAAGUGCGCAGACGAGAAGCGGCCCUACGCGGAGGGCGAGGAGGAGGAGGGGGGCGAGGAGGAGGCGCGGGAGGAGCCCCUCAAGAGCUCCAAGAACGCAGAGCCCGUGGGCAAAGAGGAGAAGGAGCUGGAGCUUAGUGACUUGGACGACUUCGACCCGCUGGAAGCAGAGCCGCCGGCGUGCGAGCUGAAGCCGCCCUUCCACUCCCUGGACGGCGGUCUGGAGCGCGUCCCCGCCGCGCCCGACGGCCCGGUCAAGGAGGCCUCAGGCGCGCUCCGGAUGUCUCUGGCCGCGGGUGGCGGAGCUGCUCUGGACGAGGACCUGGAGAGGGCCCGGAGCUGUCUCCGCAGCGCGGCGGCCGGGCCGGAGCCACUGCCGGGCGCAGAGGGCGGCCCUCAGGUCUGCGAGGCCAAGCUGGGGUUUGUGCCGGCGGGGGCGUCGGCAGGCCUGGAGGCUAAGCCGCGCAUCUGGUCCCUGGCCCACACAGCCACCGCCGCCGCCGCCGCCGCCACCUCCCUGAGCCAGACUGAGUUUCCGUCGUGCAUGCUCAAGCGCCAAGGUCCCGCGGCCCCUGCGGCUGUGUCCUCCGCGCCCGCCACGUCCCCGUCUGUGGCCCUUCCCCACUCUGGCGCCCUGGACAGGCACCAGGACUCCCCGGUAACCAGUCUCAGAAACUGGGUGGACGGGGUCUUCCACGACCCCAUCCUCAGGCACAGCACUUUGAACCAGGCCUGGGCCACCGCCAAGGGCGCCCUCCUGGACCCCGGGCCUCUGGGACGCUCGCUGGGGGCGGGCGCGAACGUGCUGACUGCACCCCUGGCCCGCGCCUUUCCGCCUGCCGUGCCCCAGGACGCCCCAGCUGCAGGCGCCGCCAGGGAGCUGCUCGCCCUGCCCAAGGCCGGCGGCAAACCCUUCUGCGCCUGAGGCGGGCGGGUCCCGAGCCCAGGAGGGAACCCGCGCUCAGGCGGACGGCGCCGACUCUUUUCACUGAGUUUCCAGAGGAAGACUAGCGCGGCCACCGCGAAGCCGCCAACCCACCGGAGAGGGGGCUUCUGAACUUGGACUCCUGGGAACAUGGACAAGCCCGGCGCUGCCACGCCGGGGCCUCCACCGCCUGGGCCUGAGCCUGACCGGGCCAUUCCCAAAUUUGGGACGCGGAAGGAGAGGCUCUCGGAGCAGAAGAGGCCAGAUACCCUGAAGCAUAAAGUUUACGUCAAAAGUUUACAUGGAGAAGGCGGUUCCGUUCUGAAGCGUGGUCUGCUGUCCCCUGGGCGUGAGGCCUCCUGGGCCUGUCGGGCCUCCGAUUUCAUCCUCAGCACGUAAUGCUCACCAACAGCACUUGCACUGAGUUGACUCUUGCACACUCUUGACUCCAUAAUAUGAUGCUUUUUAAGAUGUAUGUUCACACCAAUAAUUGCCUGCUUCAGAGGCUAAUAUAACAAAACCAAUAAAACCGAGUGAUGGUG